CUGACUUAAGACAUAACUUCAGGUGACACAAUUUUUUUUUGUUUCCUCCUAGAAAAAAAAAAAGUAAUUUUGACAUUUAAAGUCUGUAGUUCAUUUUGAGUUACAUUUCUGUAUGGUGCAAGAUAUGUGCAAUGGCUAGUACUAUGUGUCAACUUGUCUAGGCUAUACUGCUCAGCUGUGUGGUCAAACAGUAGUCUAGAUGUUGCUGUGAAGGUAUUUUGUAGAUGUGAUCAACAUUUACAAUCAGUUGAUUUUAAGUAAAGCAGUUUAACUUCCAUAAUGUGGAUGGGCCUCAUCCAAUUAGUUGAAGGUGUUAAGAGAAAAGACCAAGGUUUCCUGGAAAAGGAAUUCUACCACAAGACUAACAUAAAAAUGCGCUGUGAGUUUCUAGCCUGCUGGCCUGCCUUCACUGUCCUGGGGGAGGCUUGGAGAGACCAGGUGGACUGGAGUAGACUGUUGAGAGACACUGGUCUGGUGAAGAUGUCCAGGAAACCACGAGCCUCCAGCCCAUUGUCCAACAACCACCCACCAACACCAAAGAGGUUCCCAAGACAACCCGGAAGGGAAAAGGGACCCAUCAAGGAAGUUCCAGGAACAAAAGGCUCUCCCUAAAAGACCGCCGCUUCAAAAAAACCUGAGGAAUGGAGUGGGCCAACACUAUCCAGCCACUCUGACCAGCCGAACGAGGAACUCAAUCAAAAUGAGCCAUAGCGGGACCACAAGGGCAAGGAGACCACCACCUUCUCCAGUCUCUCUUCGGACAGCCAGUAAUUCCCGGGCAAGGCCAGAGACUUCAAGUCUAUCUGAAAAGUCUCCAGAGGUCUAACCCCAGAUAAAUAGCCAACAGGGUGUAGAGUACAUUUUACACCCCAAAGAGUGUGCCCCAUGGUGAUGAAAAUAAAGUGAACAUGUUGCAAAAUGA